ACGCAUUACAGAGCUCUGGAGCAGCCCGCAGUGGAAAGUUGGAGCUGAGGUGUGUGGCAGGCAGAUGAGGGAGCAGAGAACUGCUGAACAGAGUGAGACUCAGAGGACGUGGUUGAGCAUGGCUGCGACCCUGCAGUUCCUGGUUUGCCUGGUGGUAGCCAUUUGUCUCCUCUCUGGUGUGACUACAACCCAGCCCCAUGCAGGGCAGCCCAUGGACAGCACCAGCGUGGGAGGUGGCCUGCAGGAGCCAGAGGCCCCGGAAGUGAUGUUUGAGGCCACAGCCCACCCCUUACAUGGCUCCCCUUGCAGCUGCUCUGGGCUGGGCUGGAGCUGGAUGUCAUGGGGCAGCUGCACAUCCAGGAUGAGGAACUAGCGUCCACACACCCAGGCCGCCGACUCAGACUCCUCCUGCAGCACCACGUGCCCAGUGACUUGGAGGGCACUGAGCAGUGGCUGCAGCAGCUCCAGGACCUGCGGAAGGGGCCUCCUCUUAGCACUUGGGACUUUGAACAUCUGCUCCUCACAGGCCUGUCCUGCGUCUACCGGCUCCACGCAGCUAGUGAGGCUGAGGAACGGGGCCGCUGGGCCCAGGUCUUCGCUCUCCUGGCACAGGAAACACUCUGGGACCUGUGCAAAGGUUUCUGCCCCCAGGACCGGCCCCCUUCCCUGGGGUCCUGGGCCUCCAUCCUUGACCCCUUCCCCUGACCCUCCUCUUUUGUUCUUUCACCUGCCAUUACCCCCUCCCAUCUCCUCCUCAACCCCCCAGGCAGACCCAUCUUGCGCAGGGGCUUCUGUCUGGCAUCUGAUUCUUUUCACCGUGUUCAGAUCUCUGGGCUUGGCUUGCACCCUGGACACCCCCUCUCUGCUUACCCCGACCAGAUCUUGUUUCCUAGAUCUUGAGAGGCUAAGAACCCAGGCUCUGGGUCGCAAGGAGUGCGCAAGGAGUGGGCACAGAGCUAAGGGCACGACUUGCAGGCAGUGUGUGUGUGAGUGUGUGUGUGUGUGUGUGUGUGUGUGUGUGUGUGUGGAGAUCAGGGGUCAGGGUUGAGAAGUGUGUUCAAGAGAUGCUGAAGGGAAGCUGCCCCAAGUAAGGCCUGGUCAGACCUUCCAACUCCUACCCUGGCAGUCUGUGACAGGUCCUGUGGAAUUCACAGGAAUCCUCUAGGUGCUGAGCAUCCCCUUUUAGGCACAACCAAGGAUUUGGGGUCUCUGAGCCUCCAAGUUCCCAUCUGGGUUGGGAGAAUCGACUUUUUGAGUUCUGUCAGUUGGAAGAGUGGAGGGAAGCAGGGGGAGGGAGGAACAUUAUCUCUUUUGGGGUAGGGAGGCAAUAUCUCAACAAGCGUCGGGUGAAUACCUCAGAGGGGGGAGUAAGGCUGGGAGACCAAGGAGAGACAAGCGGAGGUGGGCUGGAGCAGGUGUGGCCCUGAUUCUGUGUUGCUCUUCUCAUAAAAUGUUCUGUUUCGGC